AGAAUAUAACAGCACUCCCAAAGAACUGGGUACUCAACACUGAGCAGAUCUGUUCUUUGAGCUAAAAACCAUGUGCUGUACCAAGAGUUUGCUCCUGGCUGCUUUGAUGUCAGUGCUGCUACUCCACCUCUGCGGCGAAUCAGAAGCAGCAAGCAACUUUGACUGCUGUCUUGGAUACACAGACCGUAUUCUUCAUCCUAAAUUUAUUGUGGGCUUCACACGGCAGCUGGCCAAUGAAGGCUGUGACAUCAAUGCUAUCAUCUUUCACACAAAGAAAAAGUUGUCUGUGUGCGCAAAUCCAAAACAGACUUGGGUGAAAUAUAUUGUGCGUCUCCUCAGUAAAAAAGUCAAGAACAUGUAAAAACUGUGGCUUUUCUGGAAUGGAAUUGGACAUAGCCCAAGAACAGAAAGAACCUUGCUGGGGUUGGAGGUUUCACUUGCACAUCAUGGAGGGUUUAGUGCUUAUCUAAUUUGUGCCUCACUGGACUUGUCCAAUUAAUGAAGUUGAUUCAUAUUGCAUCAUAGUUUGCUUUGUUUAAGCAUCACAUUAAAGUUAAACUGUAUUUUAUGUUAUUUAUAGCUGUAGGUUUUCUGUGUUUAGCUAUUUAAUACUAAUUUUCCAUAAGCUAUUUUGGUUUAGUGCAAAGUAUAAAAUUAUAUUUGGGGGGGAAUAAGAUUAUAUGGACUUUCUUGCAAGCAACAAGCUAUUUUUUAAAAAAAACUAUUUAACAUUCUUUUGUUUAUAUUGUUUUGUCUCCUAAAUUGUUGUAAUUGCAUUAUAAAAUAAGAAAAAUAUUAAUAAGACAAAUAUUGAAAAUAAAGAAACAAAAAGUU